CGCUUCUAGGACUUUGGUCUAAGAUCAAGUGUGUAAGUAACGCUACUGCAUAUAUCAGAGCAUUCAGUUAACUAAUUCUCAUGAAUCCAUUUCAUUGUCCUCAUCCAAAGUGUUAUCCAGUGCCUCCGCUUGUGACAUCUUUUUUACAGCUGUUGGAGGCCCCUUAUUCAUUCUGUUUAGCAACUUUAAAAUUACAUAUUCACUGUGACUUUAAUUUAUACUUAAAACUCCAUGGAAAUUGGCAGUACUAAGAUAUCUAGAUAUUAAAGUGUGAUUAAAAUUUAAAGUUGUUAAGCAUUACUUAUGUGGAGCAUGCAGUAAUUUUCAUGAGACCUCCCACACCCUGCACUUUUAUUUUUUUACCAAAAUCUUUUUUAAGUUUUUGUUAAAACCAACUAAGUCGUAUUGCAAAAAGAGGGAUUUGAACCAUGUUUUUAAAAAUGCAAUUGUCAUUUAUAUCAUUGUCAUCUUCAUCUGAUUCCAGUGAUGAGGUUUUGCUACUUGGUGAAUCCCUACCUGGCAGCUGCUAAAGUCCCACAUUUACCAGCCACCUAGAGGGCAUAAGACACUCACUGUUCUAGCAGUGGUUGCUCACAGGGAGCCAAUCUGGACAAAGCUGAAAUGACGAUAAAUGUUAAGGGAUUGGAUUAUAGAGAGAUAAUUAAAGUUUCAUUAUAUAAACUCUAACUUUCUUUUGGCUUUUAAGAUUUAACACAUUUUUAUCUAUAGAUGUUGCUGGGCUAAUACUACACGUGUCCAGCUAUUCUCAAGAUGGCUUCUGAAUUUGCCAUAAUGGAAAGAUACAUUUAAUGCUGCAAUUUUAAAGUUAUAGCCAACCAUUUAAAGCCUUUCAGCUAUGCUUUAUGGAGGCCAGGCACUGUUUAUCAGCUGCUAAUGUCAUUUUUGGUCAAACUGGAAAGAUCUCAGCCACAGAAGACACUCCUGAAGCUGAAGGAGAAGUGCCAGAGCUUUAUCAUCAAAGAAAGGGGGAAAUAGCAAGGUGCUGGAUCAAAUACUGUUUGACUCUCAUGCAGAAUGCCCAACUCUCCAUGCAGGACAACAUAGGAGAGCUUGAUCUUGAUAAACAGUCUGAACUUAGAGCUUUAAGGAAAAAAGAACUAGAUGAGGAGGAAAGCAUUCGGAAAAAAGCUGUGCAGUUUGGAACCGGUGAACUGUGUGAUGCCAUCUCUGCAGUAGAAGAGAAAGUGAGCUACUUGAGACCUUUAGAUUUUGAAGAAGCCAGAGAACUUUUCUUAUUGGGUCAGCACUAUGUCUUUGAGGCAAAAGAGUUCUUUCAGAUUGAUGGUUAUGUCACUGACCAUAUUGAAGUUGUCCAAGACCACAGUGCUCUGUUUAAGGUGCUUGCAUUCUUUGAAACUGACAUGGAGAGACGGUGCAAGAUGCAUAAACGCAGAAUAGCCAUGCUAGAGCCCCUAACUGUAGACCUGAAUCCACAGUAUUAUCUGUUGGUCAACAGACAGAUCCAGUUUGAAAUUGCACAUGCUUACUAUGAUAUGAUGGAUUUGAAGGUUGCCAUUGCUGACAGGCUAAGGGAUCCUGAUUCACACAUUGUAAAAAAAAUAAAUAAUCUUAAUAAGUCAGCACUGAAGUACUACCAGCUCUUCUUAGACUCCCUGAGAGACCCAAAUAAAGUAUUCCCUGAGCAUAUAGGGGAAGAUGUUCUUCGCCCUGCCAUGUUAGCUAAGUUUCGAGUUGCCCGUCUCUAUGGCAAAAUCAUUACUGCAGAUCCCAAGAAAGAGCUGGAAAAUUUGGCAACAUCAUUGGAACAUUACAAAUUUAUUGUUGAUUACUGUGAAAAGCAUCCUGAGGCCGCCCAGGAAAUAGAAGUUGAGCUAGAACUUAGUAAAGAGAUGGUUAGUCUUCUCCCAACAAAAAUGGAGAGAUUCAGAACCAAGAUGGCCCUGACUUAAUCCUUGUUUUUAAAGAAAGGAAAUGUGCAAUAUUGAAGUGAUCUUUUUCCCUAGUCAGACAGGCCCAAUUCCAUUGUGAUGUUUACCUUUAUAGCCAGGUGAGUGCAGUUUGAACUUGAGAUACAGUCAACUGAGUGUUUGCUAGGAUCCUAAGGAACAUAAAGUUAAUUAAAAACUUACACCUAAUUAUGUAAAUUGCCUUGUUAAAGACAUGUGAUUUGUAUUUUAGAUGCUUGUUUCCUAUUAAAAUACAGACAUUUCUACCCUCAGUUUCUAAAUGUAGACUAUUUGUUGGCUAGUACUUGAUAGAUUCCUUGUAAGAAAAAAUGCUGGGUAAUGUACCUGGUAACAAGCCUGUUAAUAUAUUAAGAUUGAAAAAGUAACUUCUAUAGUUACUCCUUCUAAAAUAUUUGACUUCCUAAAUUCCCCCCACCCAAAAUCUUUCCCUUUUGAAAAUACUAAAAACUAAGUUAUGUUAUUAUAAAGUGUAAAAUGGUUUGUCUUAAUUAUAGGAGAAAAAGGCCUUGUUAGAAAUAAAAUAAACUGACUUAUUUCACUAAUGAAAA